GCAAAGCCAUCCCGGCGGCUAAGGAGAGCGGGCAGGCAAGGAGAUUCCGGGCCAGGGUCGCGGCGGCAGUCGGCAAGCGUUCGAUUCUCUGGCGUUGGAUCGCGAGCGGUGUCUGCUUGUCCCGCCGAGGGCUCCCAGGACAGGGCAGGGAUCUAGGGGGUUUGCGCACCUGCUUUUUAAUGCCCCGCCCCCCCUUUUUUUUUUAAAGUGGAGGGGGUGAAAGUGAGGGAGGAGAAUGGACAGAAUACUGACUGGAACGUUAAUUCGAGCAUUUCAUAUGCGAAGAGCGGAAUAACAGUUCCGUAUUCUUCUUUCAGUUUCUCCAUUAGAUUAGCUUCAUUUUCGAAUGCUCCGUUUUGCAUGCUUAAUUUUGAAACUAGCCCGUGGUUUGGCAGAAUUUGACUGAAUUCAGGGGUGAGAGUUUGAUCCAGUCCAAGUGUAUUUGAAUUUGAGCACGCAGUUCAACCAGUGUUUACAAUGGAAUUUCUGAAGACUUGUGUACUUAGAAGAAAUGCAUGCACUGCGGUUUGCUUCUGGAGAAGCAAAGUUGUCCAAAAGCCUUCAGUUAGAAGGAUUAGUACUACCUCUCCUAGGAGCACUGUCAUGCCUGCUUGGGUGAUAGAUAAAUAUGGGAAGAAUGAAGUGCUUCGAUUCACUCAGAACAUGAUGAUGCCUAUCAUACACUAUCCAAAUGAAGUCAUUGUCAAAGUUCACGCUGCCAGUGUAAAUCCUAUAGACGUUAAUAUGAGAAGUGGUUAUGGAGCUACAGCUUUAAAUAUGAAGCGUGAUCCUUUACACGUGAAAAUCAAAGGAGAAGAAUUUCCUCUGACUCUGGGUCGGGAUGUCUCUGGCGUGGUGAUGGAAUGUGGGCUUGAUGUGAAAUACUUCAAGCCUGGAGAUGAGGUCUGGGCUGCAGUUCCUCCUUGGAAACAAGGCACUCUUUCAGAGUUUGUUGUAGUCAGUGGGAAUGAGGUCUCUCACAAACCCAAAUCACUCACUCAUACUCAAGCUGCCUCUUUGCCAUAUGUGGCUCUCACAGCCUGGUCUGCUAUAAACAAAGUUGGUGGCCUGAAUGACAAGAAUUGCACAGGAAAACGUGUUCUAAUCUUAGGCGCUUCAGGCGGAGUUGGUACUUUUGCUAUACAGGUAAUGAAAGCAUGGGAUGCUCAUGUGACAGCAGUUUGCUCCCAAGAUGCCAGUGAACUUGUAAGGAAGCUUGGUGCAGACGAUGUAAUUGAUUACAAAUCUGGAAGUGUGGAAGAGCAGUUGAAAUCCUUAAAACCAUUUGAUUUUAUCCUUGAUAAUGUUGGCGGAUCCACUGAAACAUGGGCUCCAGAUUUUCUCAAGAAAUGGUCAGGAGCCACCUAUGUGACUUUGGUGACUCCUUUCCUCCUGAACAUGGACCGAUUGGGCAUAGCAGAUGGCAUGUUGCAGACAGGAGUCACUGUAGGUUCAAAGGCAUUAAAGCAUUUCUGGAAAGGAGUCCAUUAUCGCUGGGCAUUUUUCAUGGCCAGUGGCCCAUGUUUAGAUGACAUUGCAGAACUGGUGGAUGCGGGAAAGAUCCGGCCAGUUAUUGAACAAACCUUUCCUUUUUCUAAAGUUCCAGAAGCCUUCCUGAAGGUGGAAAGAGGACACGCACGAGGAAAGACUGUAAUUAAUGUUGUUUAAAUAAAAAUGCAGUUUAGUGAUUGUUGACGUUCUUAUUUGGUGAGUGCCUGUGAGCCCAAAUUUUUUUCUAGCCAUCCCUUUCAAACAUUUUUCCAGAUUAGAUUAUACAUUCCAUGAUACAAGCUUUAAAAAAUAAACACACCAUUUUGGCCAGUAAUUGAUAUAAAAAUAUCAGCACUUGGAUUUGUCUGUAGUCAGUAGAAAUUCGAAGUUUUUUCAAGCUGUUCCUUCACACUGGCUUUGCAGGUUGUUGUGGCACCUUCUGUUUUACUAGCUUAAACUACUUUAUUGUCUUUUUUGUUUUAGAGACAGGGUCUCGCUGUGUCACCCAGGCUGGAGUGCAGUGGCACAAUCACAGCUCACUGCAGCCUUGACCUUAAGCGAUUCUCCUGCUUCAGCCUCUCAAGUAGGUAGGACUACAGGUAUGCAUCACCACACCCAGCUAGUUUUUUUGUAUUUUUAGUAGAGACAGUUUUGCCAUGUUGCCCAGGCUGGUCUCAAACUCCUGGGCUUAAGUGAUCCACCAUGUCAGUCUCCCAAAGUUCUGGGAUUACAGGCGUGAACCACCCUGCUGGGCCUGAUCGUCUUAAUGUACAAUACUAAAACUUUCAGUGUAUAGAUGGAUGUUGGCAUGAAGAGAUAAUUUAAAGCUGGUUCCUUCUUGAAUUCAUCACUGAGCAGCUUUCUAACUGCCAAGGUUUCCUUUUUUGUUCCUCCACCAUAAUGUGGUCACCACAGCUCUUAAAGUUCUAAAUCUCUUAGUGUCAUAUAUAAAAAUCUGCCUGGUGAUUCAUUUGUUUAUGCUCUUAAUAUUGAAAGGUGAGAGCAGAGUUUCUAACUUUUUAAAACCCUUACAUCUUGCAUAAGGAUUAGGCCUGUUUCGGCAAUUGAAACAUGCUUCUCUGAGGGCUUUUCCAUGGAAAUUGCAGCCUUCCAAUGGAGCCCAAAGCUUGCCACUUUGAUGUCAAAUGUUUACAUUUAGAUAUCUCUCCAAUCAACCCAUUGCAGUGUGCACUUCGAAUAUUCAUUUACGGUAAGUGUUUUUACUUCCUAAUAUACUCAUCCUCAGUAUUGCACCUGAUAUGCUUGCUUGUAACUUUUGAUGUAGACCUGUUUUGAGAUUUCUGCUUGGUUUAUUCCUGUUAGACACUCGUUUGGUAGCAUGUAUGUUAGAUGUAGGCUUUUCUCUAAAAUUGUUGGUCUGGUCUUACUACCGAGUUAUUGC